CUCUUCCUGAGAAACGAGCAAACCUGAAAGCUACUCUCUCAGCUUCAGAGGGAAAAAAUGGUUGUAGAUUUCUGGACUUGGGAGCAGACAUUUCAAGAACUAAUCCAAGAGGCAAAACCCCGGGCCACAUGGACGCUGAAGUUGGAUGGCAACCUUCAGCUAGACUGCCUGGCUCAAGGGUGGAAGCAAUACCAACAGAGAGCAUUUGGCUGGUUCCGGUGUUCCUCCUGCCAGCGAAGUUGGGCUUCCGCCCAAGUGCAGAUUCUGUGCCACACGUACUGGGAGCACUGGACAUCCCAGGGUCAGGUGCGUAUGAGGCUCUUUGGCCAAAGGUGCCAGAAGUGCUCCUGGUCCCAAUAUGAGAUGCCUGAGUUCUCCUCGGAUAGCACCAUGAGGAUUCUGAGCAACCUGGUGCAGCAUAUACUGAAGAAAUACUAUGGAAAUGGCACGAGGAAGUCUCCAGAAAUGCCAGUAAUCCUGGAAGUGUCCCUGGAAGGAUCCCAUGACACAGCCAAUUGUGAGGCAUGCACUUUGGGCAUCUGUGGACAGGGCUUAAAAAGCUGCAUGACAAAGCCGUCCAAAUCCCUACUCCCCCACCUAAAGACUGGGAAUUCCUCACCUGGAAUUGGUGCUGUGUACCUCGCAAACCAAGCCAAGAACCAGUCAGCUGAGGCAAAAGAGGCUAAGGGGAGUGGGUAUGAGAAAUUAGGGCCCAGUCGAGACCCAGAUCCACUGAACAUCUGUGUCUUUAUUUUGCUGCUUGUAUUUAUUGUAGUCAAAUGCUUUACAUCAGAAUGAUGAAAAUAGGCUUGCCACUUUCUCUUAUUUUAAUUCCAUGGUAGUCAAUGAACUGGCUGCCACUUUAAUAUAACUGAAAAUUCAUUUUGAGACCAAGCAGGAUCAAGUUUGUAGAAUAAACACUGGUUUCCUAGCCAUCCUCUGAAAACAGUAUGAAACAUGACCAAGUACAUAAUGGAUUUAGUAAUAAAUAUUGUCGAAUUGCUAAAAAGUCUUCAAUCAUUCAUUCACUAAGUCACUCAGUGAUAUCAAUAUACUUAGCUCAGAAAGUGUGGGAGGCUGAAUAAUGGUGUCUCCCAACAUAUGCAUGACUUAAUCCCCAGAACCUGUAAACAUGUUACUUUACAUGGUAGAAUGGACUUUGCGGAUGUAAUUAAGGACCUUGAAAUGGUUAGAUUAUUUCAUAUUGUCCGGGUGGAUAAGAACCAGGAUUUUGUAACAGGGAGGCAACAAGCUCAAAAUCAGAAAAAAGAGAUUUGUCAAUGGAACAAGAGGUUGAAGUGCUUUGAAGUUGGAGGAAGAGGUCACAGGCAAAAAAGUACAGGCAGCCUUUAGAAACCCAAAAGGACAAAGGAACAGAUUCUCCCCUGGAGUCUGCAGAAGGAACCAGCCCUGCCUGCACAUGGCUUUAGCCCAGUGACACUGAUUUUGGACAUCUGACCUUCAGAACUGCUUGCUCAUAAACUUGUCUUGUUUUAAUGCA